AGUCCCCUCAGCGCACCUGCAUGCACACACACCACCUCACAACCACACACUGCAUGCACACACAUACACCACAGCCACACACUGUGCAUACACGCACACCCCACAACCCACAUACUGCAUGCACACACACACACCUACAAGCUGCAUGCUGCAUACACAAGUCAUACAGGAGAUAAACUCAGAGUCCCAGCCCCAAAUAGACCCCAUCUCUUGCUCAGUUGCUGUCAUCCUAGACCUGUUUCUUUCGCCACAUUUCUAUAAUCUGCCAGUGUCUGCAAGGAGAAGACAUGGGGGGUUUUCUACCUAAGGCAGAAGGGCCCGGGAGCCAACUCCAGAAACUUCUGCCCUCCUUUCUGGUCAGAGAACAAGACUGGGACCAGCACCUGGACAAGCUUCAUAUGCUGCAGCAGAAGAGGAUUCUAGAGUCUCCACUGCUUCGAGCAUCCAAGGAAAAUGACCUGUCUGUUCUUAGGCAACUUCUACUGGACUGCACCUGUGACGUUCGACAAAGAGGAGCCCUGGGGGAGACGGCGCUGCACAUAGCAGCCCUCUAUGACAACUUGGAGGCGGCCUUGGUGCUGAUGGAGGCUGCCCCAGAGCUGGUCUUUGAGCCCACCACAUGUGAGGCUUUUGCAGGUCAGACUGCACUGCACAUCGCUGUUGUGAACCAGAAUGUGAACCUGGUGCGUGCCCUGCUCACCCGCAGGGCCAGUGUCUCUGCCAGAGCCACAGGCACUGCCUUCCGCCAUAGUCCCCGCAACCUCAUCUACUUUGGGGAGCACCCUUUGUCCUUUGCUGCCUGUGUGAACAGCGAGGAGAUCGUGCGGCUGCUCAUUGAGCAUGGAGCUGACAUCAGGGCCCAGGACUCCCUGGGAAACACAGUAUUACACAUCCUCAUCCUCCAGCCCAACAAAACCUUUGCCUGCCAGAUGUACAACCUGCUGCUGUCCUAUGAUGGACAUGGGGACCACCUGCAGCCCCUGGACCUUGUGCCCAAUCACCAGGGUCUCACCCCCUUCAAGCUGGCUGGAGUGGAGGGUAACACUGUGAUGUUCCAGCACCUGAUGCAGAAGCGGAGGCACAUCCAGUGGACGUAUGGACCCCUGACCUCCAUUCUCUACGACCUCACGGAGAUCGACUCCUGGGGAGAGGAGCUGUCCUUCCUGGAGCUUGUGGUCUCCUCUGAUAAACGAGAGGCUCGCCAAAUUCUGGAACAGACCCCAGUGAAGGAGCUGGUGAGCUUCAAGUGGAACAAGUAUGGCCGGCCGUACUUCUGCAUCCUGGCUGCCUUGUACCUGCUCUACAUGAUCUGCUUUACUACGUGCUGCGUCUACCGCCCCCUUAAGUUUCGUGGUGGCAACCGCACUCAUUCUCGAGACAUCACCAUCCUCCAGCAAAAACUACUACAGGAGGCCUAUGAGACACGUGAAGAUAUCAUCAGGCUGGUGGGGGAGCUGGUGAGCAUCGUUGGGGCUGUGAUCAUCCUGCUCCUAGAGAUUCCAGACAUCUUCAGGGUUGGUGCCUCUCGCUAUUUUGGAAAGACGAUUCUUGGGGGGCCAUUCCAUGUCAUCAUCAUCACCUAUGCCUCCCUGGUGCUGGUGACCAUGGUGAUGCGGCUCACCAACACCAAUGGGGAGGUGGUGCCCAUGUCCUUUGCCCUGGUGCUGGGCUGGUGCAGUGUCAUGUAUUUCACUCGAGGAUUCCAGAUGCUGGGUCCCUUCACCAUCAUGAUCCAGAAGAUGAUUUUUGGAGACCUAAUGCGUUUCUGCUGGCUGAUGGCUGUGGUCAUCUUGGGAUUUGCCUCCGCGUUCUAUAUCAUUUUCCAGACAGAGGACCCAACCAGUCUGGGGCAAUUCUAUGACUACCCCAUGGCACUGUUCACCACCUUUGAGCUUUUUCUCACUGUUAUUGAUGCACCUGCCAACUACGACGUGGACUUGCCCUUCAUGUUCAGCAUUGUCAACUUCGCCUUCACCAUCAUUGCCACACUGCUCAUGCUCAACUUGUUCAUCGCCAUGAUGGGCGACACCCACUGGAGGGUGGCCCAGGAGAGGGAUGAGCUCUGGAGGGCCCAGGUCGUGGCCACCACAGUGAUGCUGGAGCGGAAGCUGCCUCGCUGCCUGUGGCCUCGCUCCGGGAUCUGUGGGUGCGAAUUCGGGCUGGGGGACCGCUGGUUCCUGCGGGUUGAGAACCACAAUGAUCAGAAUCCUCUGCGAGUGCUUCGCUAUGUGGAAGUGUUCAAGAACUCAGACAAGGAGGAUGACCAGGAGCAUCCAUCUGAGAAACAGCCCUCUGGGGCUGAGAGUGGGACUCUAGCCAGAGCCUCUUUGGCUCUUCCAACUUCCUCCCUGUCCCGGACCGCGUCCCAGAGCAGCAGUCACCGAGGCUGGGAGAUCCUUCGUCAAAACACCCUGGGGCACUUGAAUCUUGGACUGAACCUUAGUGAGGGGGAUGGAGAGGAGGUCUACCAUUUUUGAUUAACAUCGCUAUCACUCUUGACCUUACUCCCGGUUGGCCUGGGGGCGGGGACAGAGACGGAGACCUCUGCCUAUGCAAGUGUCUAACUUCUGUGCCUGUUAAUCAUGGGAGGGUGAGACAGAACAAUCCCUAAAGGGUCAUGCCUCACACUUCACAUCAGAAUUUCUGGCAAUGGGCAAUGGUCAUCGAUUGUCUCACGUAUUUUCUGGGCUCUUGCAAGUCACCCAUCUCAGGAAAAAGGAGGUUGGCAACUAAAGACAUGAGGCAGGGAUGCUAGAUUAAUGUCAGGACCAUUUCUCUUCUGCCCCACGCAGCCCCUAGAAAGUAGUAAGCUGUGAGGCUUUUCUGGCUCCCCAGGGCUUACGUGGGAAGAGCCAGGCAUGGCAUAGAGGUUGUGGCCCUUCUUUUUUUC